AUUCCUGUGUGAAGAGUGCCAGUGUGAAGACAGUUUUGUAAGAACUGCAAGUGCUCAGGCUGUAUGGGAAACAGAAACUUCAGCAGAUGAACUGACCUUAUGCCAUUUCCUGAUGUUUGGCAGUGACACUGAAAGAGGACCGCAUGUCCCCUCUUUAUGUGGAUUUAUCUUUUAUGAAAAGUUUGCUUUUGUCCGGGACAGUUUGUUGUCGUGAGAUACAUCAGACAAUAUAAUCAUGGGACAAGCUGAUGUCUCCAGACCGGUAAAUCCAGAUGCAGUUGAGGAAGCAGACCAGCCCACUACAGAGCCAGGCAUGGUCCUGGACAGUGUGGAAGCAGGAGACACAACACCUCCUACCAAAAGGAAGAGCAAGUUCUCAGGCUUUGGCAAGAUCUUCAAGCCCUGGAAAUGGAGGAAAAAAAAAAGUAGUGAUAAAUUUAAAGAGACUUCAGAAGUUUUAGAACGGAAAAUAUCUAUGCGAAAGCCAAGAGAAGAGCUGGUUAAAAGAGGGGUUCUGUUGGAAGACCCUGAGCAAGGUGGUGAGGAUCCAGGAAAGCCAAGCGAUGCCAUGUUAAAGAAUGGCCAUACCACCCCCAUAGGGAAUGCCAGAUCAUCUAGUCCAGUCCAAGUAGAGGAAGAGCCAGUAAGAUUAGCAAGUCUUAGGAAAGCUAUUCCAGAAGAGGACCUAAAGAAACGACUAGGCUCAACUGGAAGCCAGCCUAAUUCUGAAGCAGAGUCUGUUCCUGAGAAUGUACCCAAACCACCUUUACUUCCUCCCAAAAGACCCUUGUCCUCUUCUCAUGAAGCAAGUGAAGGGCAAGCAAAGGAUGCCACUUCCUCUGGCGGCACGGCAAGGUUCAUCAUCUCCACCUCCAUCACCACAGCACCCGCUGCCACCACUGCUGCCACAAGCCUUGCAAAGACUGUUAAUCUCUCUGUCACCCCUUCCCCAGCACCCAGGACUCUGCCUGCUGCUCCUGCCAGCACUAACACUACUGCUACCCCAAGCCUCACUCAUAUGGUCCCUGCCAAGCAGCCCCCUAUCCCUCCCCCUAAACCAGCUCACAGAAAUAGCAACCCUGUCAUUGCUGAACUGUCCCAAGCAAUAAACAGUGGUACAUUGUUAUCAAAACCGUCCCCACCCUUACCACCUAAGAGAGGCAUUCCAUCAACCUCAGUACCCACCUUGGAGUCUGCUGCUGCCAUCACCACAAAAACACCAAGUGAUGAAAGAGAGAAGAGCACGUGUUCUAUGGGCUCGGAACUACUACCAAUGAUCUCACCUCGCUCUCCGUCCCCCCCACUGCCUACUCAUAUACCUCCAGAGCCUCCACGCACCCCUCCAUUCCCUGCUAAGACUUUUCAAGUUGUGCCAGAAAUUGAGUUUCCACCAUCCUUAGAUCUACACCAGGAGAUUCCCCAGCAGGAAGAUCAGAAAAAGGAAGUCCCCAAGAGGAUACUGGACCAGAACUUUGGGGAGCCCCAUAUACCCUCUAGGCUGCCUCCACUCCCACUGCAUAUUCGAAUCCAGCAGGCCCUCACCAGCCCACUUCCCAUGACUCCUAUUCUGGAGGGUUCUCACAGAGCUCAUUCGUUGCUUUUUGAAAACAGUGACAGCUUUUCUGAGGACAGCAGUACGCUGGGUCGGACCAGGUCUCUUCCCAUCACUAUUGAAAUGCUAAAAGUUCCAGACGAUGAAGAAGAAGAGGAGCAAACCUGUCCAUCCACAUUCAGUGAAGAAAUGACACCUACCUCAGUCAUUCCUAAAUUACCACAGUGUCUACGGGAGGAAGAAGAGAAGGAGAGCGACUCUGAUUCAGAAGGUCCCAUUCAGUACCGAGAUGAAGAAGAUGAAGAUGAAAGCUAUCAGAGUGCUCUCGCCAACAAAGUGAAGAGGAAAGACACACUGGCAAUGAAGUUGAACCACAGACCCAGUGAACCAGAGUUGAACCUGAAUUCUUGGCCUUGUAAAAGCAAGGAGGAGUGGAAUGAAAUACGGCACCAGAUUGGAAACACACUGAUCCGGCGACUGAGUCAAAGACCAACACCAGAAGAACUAGAACAACGCAAUAUAUUGCAACCUAAAAAUGAAGCUGAUCGUCAGGCAGAAAAACGAGAAAUUAAACGUCGGCUCACUAGAAAGCUCAGUCAAAGGCCAACUGUCGCUGAACUCCUUGCCAGGAAGAUUCUGAGGUUUAAUGAAUAUGUAGAGGUAACAGAUGCUCAAGAUUAUGACCGGCGAGCCGACAAACCUUGGACCAAACUGACCCCUGCUGACAAGGCUGCCAUAAGAAAAGAAUUAAAUGAAUUUAAAAGCUCCGAGAUGGAGGUUCAUGAAGAGAGCAAACAUUUUACACGCUACCAUCGUCCAUGAUGCCAAAGGUUGAGAGAGGAAUCAACAUGGCUGCUUUGCUGCUUCCUUCUCCAAAGUGACAUAUGGAGGGAACUUUAGCACUUCCCAGCACAGCCAGAAUUGCAUCCUCUGGGAUCUUCUGAGGUGGACAGCACUUUGAAUGUAGCAUUUCACUGGAACAGAGUCUUAUGUGCUGCACCGGGGGCAAAACAACACUUUGUCAGUGCUUUUGAACCUUUCAAUAUUGUAGCAUGCUUGAGGAGUUUUUCCCUUACUGGCCACCAAAGUUCUGAACCACUUGCAGGUUCCAGGUUUUACUGGCUGCACCACACCCCUUCCCCUAGAUGACUGCCUGUGCAGAGACACAGUUUGCACCAUUAGCCUUACCUGCCCUGCCCUGAUUGUGAGACCCAAAUGUGUAGGCUCUAAAUUCCAGCCAUCAAAUCCAAUUCCUGGUGGGGAAAACCUUCUGGAGACCCCCAACCUUCUGAUAAAAGAGUCUCUACCUCCAGGGAAAGCCUUCUUACCACACUGGCAUAUCAGAUGAAAGCAUUGCACUGUACCUCUCGUAACACAGCAAUACAGUCCUCUUGAGGCACUCAAGCCUGAGAGGAAGCUCAGGAUCUGACAUGUUCUUCCUUUUCCUCACAAGUCAUCAUGAUUUUUUAUUUUAAAAUAAUCUGGAAGUAAUGGGAACUUAGUUUUUCCUGAACUCCAACCAGAAUCCAAAUUGGUUAGAUGAGGCCAGGCGCGGUGGCUCACGCCUGUAAUCCCAGCACUUUGGGAGGCCGAGGUGGGUGGAUCACCUGAGGUCAGGAGUUCAAGACCAGCCUGGCCAACAUGGUGAAACCCCAUCUCUACUAAAAAUACAAAAAUUAGCCAGGUGUGGUGGCGCCUGGUUGAGGCAUGAGAAUCGCUUGAACCCAGGAGGUGGAGGUUGCAGUGAGCCAAGAUCAUGCCUACUGCACUCCAGCCUGGGCAACAAAGUGGGACUCUGUCUUAAAAAAAAAAAAAAAAAAAAAAUCGGUUAGAUGAGAAAGCAUGUAUAUUUUCUAUAUACAAAAACAAGAAAGGCGUUUUGAGCCCCUGUGCUCAGGCCCACUCCCACACUGUGGAGUGUACUUUCAUUUUCAAUAAAUCCCCUUAUUCCUUCCUUGCAAAAAAAAAAAAAAAAAAAGCCUUAGCCAGAUUCAGUGGCUCACGCCUGUAAUCCCAACACUUUGGGAGGCUGAGGCGGGUGGAUCACCUGAGUUCAGGAGUUCAAGACCAGCCUGGCCAACAUGGCAAAACCCUGUCUCUACUAAAAAGUAAAAAAAAUUAGCCGGGCAUGGUGGCUUGUGCCUUGUAGUCCCAGCCACUGGGGAGGCUGAGGCGGGAGAAUUGCUUGAACCUGGGAGGUGGAGAUUGCAGUGAGCCGAGAUCGCGCCACUGCACUCCAGCCUGGGUGACAGAGCGAGACUCCGUCUCAAAAAAAAAAAAAAAGCCUUAAUAUUAAUGCUAACGUGGCAGAAAACUAGCAGGUUACAUUUUAUAGGCUAUUGUAGUUUUAUUUACCAAAUGAUAUUCUCUAAAUCACUUCGACCAAUAAAUGUAUUCUCCUCCUUAAAGCAGAGUUGUAUCAACUCUGUGGGAGCAUUUAUGAGCUGUCAGUCCCCACACUUCUAGCCAGAAUCACAAUAAGGUCUGGCUGGGUGUGGGGUGCUGCAUAGGAAAGGGUCUCUGGAGAAGCAAGAAGGGCACAAUCAUGGCCCACUGCUCCCCUCUUCUUCUCAGUGCUCUUUGCCCUCUCCUGCUGCGUGCUUCCUCUUCACUCCAGUGCUGAUCCUCCUGCUCUCUCUGGCAGCUUCCACCUCACCCGCCCCUCUUCCACACUAUAACCAGUAUGGUUGGUGCUGGGGCAUUGACUCAGCCCCCCUGCUUUCUGCAUUUGUAAUAGAUAUUAAUAUGAUUUCCUAAAACAGAAGAUUUUGUUGCUUUCUUUGAACUUGUAUUGAAAACCAUACAGUCUCACUGUUUUGCUUUAAUUCCUAUCCACACUAUAAAUGGAAGAAAAAAAUUAAUAGCUUCUGUUUAAUCUGAUGAAUGUGGCUUUUUUUCCCUUCACUUUAAUGUUCAAGAAGUUGUGGCUAUUUCAUAGAUUUCUUCUGAUUUAUUCUGUGGGUCCCUGUUAUCUGUUCUUUAUGUAAUCUUUCAGUAGAUUUUCAUCCUUUCAUAUCCACAUUCUUAUGUGGACUUGCUGAAGAAACAGAAUAUCAGUUCAAAACAAAACCUAGGCCAGGCAUGGUGGUUCACGCCUAUAAUCUCAGCACUUUGGGAAGCCAAGGCGGUCAGGAGUUUGAGACCAGCCUGACCAACAUGAUGAAACCCUGUCUCUACUAAAAAUACAAAAAUUAGCCUGGCGUGGUGGCACGCAUCUGUAAUCCCAACUACUCAGGACGCUGAGGCAGGAGAGUCGCUUGAACCCAGGAGGCGGAGAUUGCAGUGAGCCAAGAUUGCACCACUGCACUCCAGCCUGGGCAACAGAGCGAGACUCCAUCAAAAAAAAAAAAAAAAAAGAAGGAAGGAAGGAAAGCAAGCCCUGAAUCCACAUCUCCUUGAAGUUUUUUUUGUUUUAUUUUGUUUUUGAGACAGAAUUUUGCUCUUGUUGCCCAGGCCGGAGUGCAAUGGUGCAAUCUCAGCUCACUGCAACCUCCGCCUCCCGGGUUGAGGCGAUUCUCCUACCUCAGCCUCCCAAGUAGCUAGGAUUACAGGCAUGAGCCACCACGCCUGGCUAAUUUUAUAUUUCUAGUAGAGAUGAGGUUUCUCCAUGUUGGUCAGGCUGGUCUCAAACUCCCGACCUCAGGUGAUCCACCCACCUCAGCCUCCCAAAGUGGUGGGAUUACAGGCAUGAGCCACCGUGCCGAGCCUUCCUUGAAGUUUUUUGUUUGGUUUUGAUUUGUUUUGUUUUGUUUUGUUUUGUUUUGUUUUUGGAGAUAGGGUCUCACUCUGUUACCCAUGCUGGAGUGCAGUGGCACAAUCUUGGCUCAGAGCAACCUCUGCCUCCCAGGCUCAAGCAAUCCUCCCACUUCAGUCUAAGUAGCUGGGACUACAGGCACGUGCCACCAGGCCCAGCUAAUUUUUGUGUUUUGUUAGAGAUGAGGUUUUGCCAUAUUGCCCAGGCUCGUCUUGAACACCGGGGCUCAAGGAAUCUGCCCAUCUUCGCCUCCCAAAGUUCUGAGAUAGCAGGUGUGAGUCAUCAUGCCCAGCCUCCUUGAAGUUUACUAACAAUUGGGAUAACUGAGGGAAGAGAAGUGACAAUUCCACUCAGUCUAUUAGAGGUCUGGAUAUAAGGUAGCCACACAAUAACUCUAACUUGACUUCUAACCAUUCUAUCUUAUUGAUUUGGAGGCUGUCUUCUGCCAGAUUUUUUGUGGCUUGAGAUGAUAUUUUCGAACCCUUCUUUCACUACCUUUCUUACCCUUAAUGUGCCAAGCUUGAAACAGGAUUUGAUUUCCUGAGCUACUUGUUCGCCUUCUGUGCGUCACCAAGUAAUCUGGUUCAUCUUUCGUCUCAUUCAUGUUAUUUUCAAGUGAAACAAGACAUUUUGGGGGUCAAGUCUCUUUGGGUGUUUUGUUUUUAUGUAUAUAAAAAUGGAUUUUGUGUUCCCUUUCCAUGUAAGUACCAACUUAUAUGGAAACUCACAAUCAUAAUGUAAAGAAGAAAUGAAAGCCUGGUGUAUUGUACUUCAAGAUGCCUCCCUGAUGUAUAGAAUCUCCUUGUAAAAUAAAUAAUUGCAUUGUAUAUCAGUCUUCUCAUCAAUAUUAAUUAUUAAAUAUUUUAGAAUUUUUAAAUACCAA